GAAAAAUUCGUUUUCUAUACAUCUCCUGCCCUCCAGAGGCCUGUGCUCUCCUUGGACAACCAAGAAACCAAGAUAUAAGCAAGUUGAGUGUUUAAAUAGAAUCCAAAGCAGUGUGUGCUAAGUGCCACAUGGGUAAGAGAGGUGGAGAGGAAUUCAGAGGUGGGGGCAGUGCCACGGCCUGGGAAGGGAAGGGACAGGAAGGGAAGUUUCUCCCCAGGGCUGACAUGUUGUUGGUGCUUGUUAGGAAGUGAUUGAACGGAGGAGAAGACAUGGGACUUGAAACGUCAGGAAGAACAGAGGAUUUGGAGUACUGAGCACAAGACAGAUUCACACUCUGAAAAAAUUAAGAUUUAUUUGGAAAAAUGUUUUCAUCAAUGAAAACAGCCAUCGCCCUGGAGCCUUACUGAAAAGCUGGAUAAUCCCAGCUGGUGAGGAGGAGGACCUCAGGUCUACCCUGGUCAGUCAAAGAUGGCAGGAACCUCUGAGACUUUCUGGCUCCUGAAUACACAUAGUGGUUUUGGCUUAAGGGAGGUUGCAGAGUUUUCAGCUUGUCUCUUCGCUGUCCUGAAAGCUGAACUGACUGUUCAUCCAUCCCUUCCUCCCACUGUUUAUCCUUAUCCCCUGUGGCUGAUGUAACAAAUUGCCACAAAGGUAGUGGCUUAAAAUGACACAGAUGUCUCUUCCUUCUGGAGAUGGGAAUCUGAAGUCAUUGUGACUGCGCUAAAGUCAAGGUGUCAGCAGGGCUGUGUUCCUCUGGAGGCUCCAGGGGAGAAUCCUUUUCCUUGCCUCUGCCAGCUUCUAGAGGCCACCCCCCGUCCUUCACUGGUGACCCACCCCUCUCUCUAUUAUCGAAACCAGCAGCACAGAGCACCCUCAACUCGAGCUCUCUCUGACCUCUCCCUUUGUAGUCACAUGGCUCUCUCUCUUUGAUCUUCCUGCCCCCCUUACAAGGACACAUGAUGACAUUGGACCCACCCUCCCCAGCUCGGAGUCUUUAACUCAGUCACAUCUACGGAGUCCCUUUGGCCACAUAAGAUUGGCCUUAAGAGAAGGACGGAGCCACAUACUGCUGACGGCCCAGAACUGGCAGAGAGAAGGUUGCCAUGGCUGCUGUUGACAGUUUCUACCUCUUGUACAGGGAAAUCGCCAGGUCUUGCAAUUGCUAUAUGGAAGCUCUAGCUUUGGUUGGAGCCUGGUAUACGGCCAGAAAAAGCAUCACUGUCAUCUGUGACUUUUACAGCCUGAUCAGGCUGCAUUUUAUCCCCCGCCUGGGGAGCAGAGCAGACUUGAUCAAGCAGUAUGGAAGAUGGGCCGUUGUCAGCGGUGCAACAGAUGGGAUUGGAAAAGCCUACGCUGAAGAGUUAGCAAGCCGAGGUCUCAAUAUAAUCCUGAUUAGUCGGAACGAGGAGAAGUUGCAGGUUGUUGCUAAAGACAUAGCCGACACGUACAAAGUGGAAACUGAUAUUAUAGUUGCGGACUUCAGCAGCGGUCGUGAGAUCUACCUUCCAAUUCGAGAAGCCCUGAAGGACAAAGACGUUGGCAUCUUGGUAAAUAACGUGGGUGUGUUUUAUCCCUACCCGCAGUAUUUCACUCAGCUGUCCGAGGACAAGCUCUGGGACAUCAUAAAUGUGAACAUUGCCGCCGCUAGUUUGAUGGUCCAUGUUGUGUUACCGGGAAUGGUGGAGAGAAAGAAAGGUGCCAUCGUCACGAUCUCUUCUGGCUCCUGCUGCAAACCCACUCCUCAGCUGGCUGCAUUUUCUGCUUCUAAGGCUUAUUUAGACCACUUCAGCAGAGCCUUGCAAUAUGAAUAUGCCUCUAAAGGAAUCUUUGUACAGAGUCUAAUCCCUUUCUAUGUAGCCACCAGCAUGACAGCACCCAGCAACUUUCUGCACAGGUGCUCGUGGUUGGUGCCUUCGCCAAAAGUCUAUGCACAUCAUGCUGUUUCUACUCUUGGGAUUUCCAAAAGGACCACAGGAUAUUGGUCCCAUUCUAUUCAGUUUCUUUUUGCACAGUAUAUGCCUGAAUGGCUCUGGGUGUGGGGAGCAAAUAUUCUCAACCGUUCACUACGUAAGGAAGCCUUAUCCUGCACAGCCUGAGUCUGGAUGGCCACUUGAGAAGUUUUGCCAACUCCUGGGAACCUCGAUAUUCUGACAUUUGGAAAAACACAUUUAAUUUAUCUCCUGUGUUUCAUUGCUGAUUAUUCAGCAUACUGUUGAUUCGUCAUUUGCAAAACACACAUAAUACCGUCAGAGUGCUGUGAAAAACCUUAAGGGUGUGUGGAUGGCACAGGAUCAAUAAUGCCUGAGGCUGAUUGACGACAUCUACAUUUCAGUGCUUUUUCCCUAAGCUGUUUGAAAGUUACGCUUUUCUGUUGUUCUAGAGCCACAGCAGUCUAAUAUUGAAAUAUAAUAUGAUUUGUCAGGUCUUAUAAUUUCAGAUGUUGUUUUUUAAGGGAAAUUGACCAUUUCACUAGAGGAGUUGUGCUGGUUUUUAAAUGUGCAUCAAGAAAGACUACUGAAAAGUAUUAUUUUGUAACUAAGAUUGCUGGUACUAUUAGGAAAAAUCUGUGUGUAUUGUAUAGCUCUAGCUGUUUGACUAUCUGUAAUGAAAAUGCUGCACUUCAACUGGUAUUUCAUUAGAGAACCGUGUGUGUGCGUGUGUGUGGUGCCUUUGAGCAACUUUAUUUAUGGUUACCAUAUUUUUAAAAAGAUUUUUUGUCAGGGUGACUUAACAUGGACUCUUAUAGGGUAUUAAAACAAUCUAGAUUAUUCCUUUUCAUCCUAAAUAAGCCUACCAAAUUUCAUGCUGUUGGUUUGCCAUGAAUGAUAUUACUUCCUACAUUAUAUUUGUGUUUUUUCAAAUCUGCUAUGGAAUGAACUUAUUCCUAGAUUUGGAUAUGUAAGAGAAACCUGCAGUCAUCUUUUGAUUUAUAAGGCAAUUCUUGUGGAUAAAUAGUGAUUUCUCAGCCUCUGACCCAUUUUAUAACUGAAAUUUAGCCCUUUAGAGCUUGUUAUAUCUGGUUUUCCUACGUUUUUCUAUGUAAUAUUAUUCCAUUCCAGUAGCAUUAUUGAUAGAAAUAGUAAGUAUUUAUGGAAUAGUAAAAUAUGGACAAAUUACGUGUGUGACAUAUCUGUCAAUAUAAGUUAGAAGCUUAUUCUUGGUUUGUGUAAUGAAUUUAUGUAUUGUAGUGAAUACCUUUACUGGUGUGAAGAUAAUUAUGCACAAACCCUCACAAUACGCGUUAACAUUGAAACCUGUGAAAUGUCCUUAGUUUGGGUCAUAUAAAGCCAACCAUUUUUGAGGACCAUGUACCUAGUGCUUUGAAAACUCUAAGUCACUAUAUGAAUAUGACAAUAUGUGCACAUUUAAAAUUCAGAGCUCGGCAUUGUGAUACUGAUGCAGAAGCUAGUAGAUUGGUUAAAAGUCUGGACUUCUGUGGCAUUUUUUUCGUGACGUGAUAAUCUAUCAUAAGCAGACCUAAGCACAGUUUUAUGAACACAAUUUUGCCCAUGACAUUGCCUACAGGAUUUCCAGAUGUGACUUGCACUCAGAAGAUCAGUGGUCAACUUCAGAAGCUCUUCCACGCUUAGAUCAUGUCUUCAGAACUUAGAUGUGAAAAUCUACACACUGGGAGAUGCUGUGAGCCCCAAGGUUUUGAUGGAGUUUGCUUGGAAUCCUCUUGACUUCAUGCCACAUUGACGUGAACUUUGAUGUAUAAUAAGCAGCAGCAACUUCAUGUGAAAAUAUGGUCAGGUAGUUAUAUGUAAGGUUACGUGGUCCAGUAAUGUCUUAGAUUGAUAAAUUAGGUAUGGAAUCCAUCAGUGUUACGUGAUGAGAAUAGGUGAACACACCUUGUCAGUGAUGAUGUAAACUUCUCUCCUUGGCAGGACAUGGGCAAACAUGCUGAUUGGUGCAAAUGUGGUGCCGAGCUGUCCAUAGCUGCAGUGAAAGAUGAAGAGCAAGACCUUCUCUAGGUUUUCUAGCUUUCAUUAAAUGUAUUUUUUUCCCCAGAGCUAAUUUGAAAGUUGAUUGGACCACUGUGGAUGGGGUGUCAUUAAGAAUGUGGGAAAUAGGGGCCGAGUGCGGUGGCUCACACCUGUAAUCCCAGCAGUUUGGAAGGCCAGGGCAGGUGGAUCGCUUGAUCCCAGGAGGUCGAGACCAGCCUGGGGAACACAUCCUGUCUCUACAAAAAAUACAAAAAUUAGCCAGGCAGGGUGGUGCAUGCCUGUAGUCCCAGCUACUUGGGAGGCUGAGGCAGGAGAAUUUUUUGAGCCCAGGAUGCAGAGGUUGAAGUGAGCCAAGAUCGUGCCACUGCACUCCAGCCUUGAGACAGAGCGAGACCCUGUCUCAAAAAAAAAAAAAGAACGUGGGAAAUAUGAACCUUUGAAAGUUAAUCUGUGAAUUGAAAGUUUAACAAUAAAAGUAGUUGUUUGUUUCCUUUGGAAGAGUUUUGUUCCAGAUGUUUGUAAUUUGGUUGUUUGUAAUUUGGAAUGAGAGAAUUUUUUUUUCUUAGGAGUGAUUGCAAGAAAUUAACAUGAACAACAGUGGUCAUAACUGAUUAAAAGCUGACACGUCAGUAACAAAA